ACUUCAGCCUCCCGAUAAGCUGAGAUUACAGGUGCGUACCACCAUGCCUGGCUAAUUUUUUUUUUUUUUUUUUAGAUGGAGUCUUGCUCUAUCGCCCAGGCUGGAGUGCAGUGGCGCGAUCUUGACUCACUGCAAGCUCUGCCUCCCGGGUUCACGCCAUUGUCCUGCCUCAGCCUCUGGAGUAGCUGGGACUACAGGUGCCCGCCACCAUGCCCAGCUAGUUGUUUUUUUUUUUUUUUUUUUAGUGGAGACGGUGUUUCACCGUGUUAGCCAGGAUGAUUUUGAUCUCCUGACCUUGUGAUCCACUCGCCUUGGCCUCCCAAAGUGCUGGGAUUACAGGCGUGAGCCACCGCGCCCGGCCAUGCCUGGCUAAUUUUUAUAUUUUUAUUUUAUUUUAUUUUUGAAGCAGAGUCUCGCUCUGUUACUCAGGCUGGAGUGCAGUGACCCAAUCUCAGUUCACUGCAACCUCUGCCUCCCGGGUUCAAGUGAUUGUUCAGCCUCAGCCUCCCAAGUAGCUGGGAUUACAGGCAUGUGCCACCAUGCCAGACUAAUUUUUUUUUAUUUUUAGUAGAGACAGUGUUUCACCAUGUUAGCCAGGCUGAUCUUGAACUCCUGAUCUCAGGUGAUCCACCUGCCUUGGCCUCCCAAAGUGUUGGGAUUACAGGUGUGAGUCACUGCGCCGGCCUAAUUUUUGUAUUUUUAGUAGAGAUGGGAUUUCACCAUGUUGGCCAGCCUAGCCUCAAACUCCUGACUUCAGGUGAUUGGCCCACCUUGGCCUCCCAAAGUGCUGGGAUUACAGGCCUGAGCCACGGUGCCUGGUUUAGUAUGCAUUCUUGACUGGGGAAAAUUGCAGUGAGUUUAUUAACCACUUAACCUCUCAGAACUGAACAAAGACAACAUUGUUCCUGGAACGCCCUCUUUUUAAAAAAGGUAGAACUUUAGACUUCAUAGCACUGAAUUAACCUGCACUGAAAGCUGUUUACCUGCAUUUGUUCACUUUUGUUGAAAGUGACCAUGUCUCAAGUUCAAGUGCAAGUUCAGAACCCAUCUGCUGCUCUCUCAGGGAGCCAAAUACUGAACAAGAACCAGUCUCUUCUCUCACAGCCUUUGAUGAGUAUUCCUUCUACUACUAGCUCUCUGCCCUCUGAAAAUGCAGGUAGACCCAUUCAAAACUCUGCUUUACCCUCUGCAUCUAUUACAUCCACCAGUGCAGCUGCAGAAAGCAUAACCCCUACUGUAGAACUAAAUGCACUGUGCAUGAAACUUGGAAAAAAACCAAUGUAUAAGCCUGUUGACCCUUACUCUCGGAUGCAGUCCACCUAUAACUACAACAUGAGAGGAGGUGCUUAUCCCCCGAGGUACUUUUACCCAUUUCCAGUUCCACCUUUACUUUAUCAAGUGGAACUUUCUGUGGGAGGACAGCAAUUUAAUGGCAAAGGAAAGACAAGACAGGCUGCGAAACACGAUGCUGCUGCCAAAGCGUUGAGGAUCCUGCAGAAUGAGCCCCUGCCAGAGAGGCUGGAGGUGAAUGGAAGAGAAUCCGAAGAAGAAAAUCUCAAUAAAUCUGAAAUAAGUCAAGUGUUUGAGAUUGCACUUAAACGGAACUUGCCUGUGAAUUUCGAGGUGGCCCGGGAGAGUGGCCCACCCCACAUGAAGAACUUUGUGACCAAGGUUUCGGUUGGGGAGUUUGUGGGGGAAGGUGAAGGGAAAAGCAAGAAGAUUUCAAAGAAAAAUGCCGCCAUAGCUGUUCUUGAGGAGCUGAAGAAGUUACCGCCCCUGCCUGCAGUUGAACGAGUAAAGCCUAGAAUCAAAAAGAAAACAAAACCCAUAGUCAAGCCACAGACAAGCCCAGAAUAUGGCCAGGGGAUCAAUCCGAUUAGCCGACUGGCCCAGAUCCAGCAGGCAAAAAAGGAGAAGGAGCCAGAGUACACGCUCCUCACAGAGCGAGGCCUCCCGCGCCGCAGGGAGUUUGUGAUGCAGGUGAAGGUUGGAAACCACACUGCAGAAGGAACGGGCACCAACAAGAAGGUGGCCAAGCGCAAUGCAGCCGAGAACAUGCUGGAGAUCCUUGGUUUCAAAGUCCCGCAGGCGCAGCCCACCAAACCCGCACUCAAGUCAGAGGAGAAGACACCCAUAAAGAAACCAGGGGAUGGAAGAAAAGUAACCUUUUUUGAACCUGGCUCUGGGGAUGAAAAUGGGACUAGUAAUAAAGAGGAUGAGUUCAGGAUGCCUUAUCUAAGUCAUCAGCAGCUGCCUGCUGGAAUUCUUCCCAUGGUGCCCGAGGUCGCCCAGGCUGUAGGAGUUAGUCAAGGACAUCACACCAAAGAUUUUACCAGGGCAGCUCCGAAUCCUGCCAAGGCCACGGUAACUGCCAUGAUAGCCCGAGAGUUGUUGUAUGGGGGCACCUCGCCCACAGCCGAGACCAUUUUAAAGAAUAACAUCUCUUCAGGCCACGUACCCCAUGGACCUCUCACGAGACCCUCUGAGCAACUGGACUAUCUUUCCAGAGUCCAGGGAUUCCAGGUUGAAUACAAAGACUUCCCCAAAAACAACAAGAACGAAUUUGUAUCUCUUAUCAAUUGCUCCUCUCAGCCACCUCUGAUCAGCCAUGGUAUCGGCAAGGAUGUGGAGUCCUGCCAUGAUAUGGCUGCGCUGAACAUCUUAAAGUUGCUGUCUGAGUUGGACCAACAAAGUACAGAGAUGCCAAGAACAGGAAACGGACCAAUGUCUGUGUGUGGGAGGUGCUGAACCUUUUCUGGCCAUGAACCAUUAUAAAAUCCCAACAUAUAUACUGAAAAUACUGAAACUGCUUUGAAAAUUUGGAAUUUCUGAUACCUCCAGUGGGCCGAGAGACACGGUGGGUAAAGGAUGUGGGCAGCAGCAGGGAAGACAACAGAAACACAAGGAGGCGGCUGUGGCCGGGCUGGACUGUGCUGGGGUUUGUUGUGAUGGCCACUCGGUGACCUGGCGGUCCCUACGCAAUAGCAGCUGCCUGUGGGGAAGAAGGGCUGCCCAGCCAGCUGGUUCUCCCGGGACACCAGCAGAUCCACACCCUGGGCACCUCCGUGUUUGGUCUUUUUUUUCCCCUGUGUGAAAGAAGAAACGGCACGACCCCUUCUCAAGCUGGCUCACUCAGACACAUUGGGACAAACCCUGGACAGCCAUGCCAGAGAGAGGCCUUUGACCGGCCCCAGAGCUAAAAGCACCAGAGAAAAUCAAAUGCUUCCUACUCAGCGUGACCCAACUUUUCUAGUGUGCCACGGCCCCACCACCUCCUGCAGUACCCACACCAUCACCACUGCUUUCUCUUCCAACAGUGAUCUGUAUUCUUAGUUUCAUUAUUUUCUUUUGAUUGAUAUGACACUAUAUAAAAUUUUCAUUUGAGAAUUUCUCAAUUGUAUCUAGUUAAAUAGCACAGUUUGGAAACUUGUCUGAGACUGACUUUAUCAAUAAUCUAACCGACAAAGAUCAUAUCCAUGUGUAUGUGGUUAGACAUUUUUAUUUCAUUGACUAACCCAGGACAGUUUCAGUGAUGCAAAUUGUGUGCCCUCUGGUUCAGCUGAAACAGUCCUGGACUUUCAAAAACCUUGAAUAAGUCUCCCACAGUUGUAUAAAUUGGACAAUUUAGGAAUUUUAAACUUUAGAUGAUCAUUUGGUUCCAUUUUUAUUUCAUUUUUAUUUUUGUUAAUGCAAACAGGACUUAAAUGAACUUUGAUCUCUGUUUUAAAGAUUAUUAAAAAACAUUGUGUAUCUAUACAUAUGGCUCUUGAGGACUUAGCUUUCACUACACUACAGGAUAUGAUCUCCAUGUAGUCCAUAUAAACCUGCAGAGUGAUUUUCCAGAGUGCUCGAUACUGUUAAUUACAUCUCCAUUAGGGCUGAAAAGAAUGACCUACGUUUCUGUAUACAGCUGUGUUGCUUUUGAUGUUGUGUUACUGUACACAGAAGUGUGUGCACUGAGGCUCUGCGUGUGGUCCGUAUGGAAAGCCUGGUAGCCCUGCGAGUUAAGUACUGCUUCCAUUCAUUGUUUACGCUGGAAUUUUUCUCCCCAUGGAAUGUAAGUAAAACUUAAGUGUUUGUCAUCAAUAAAUGGUAAUACUAAAUUUUUUUGUUAAUUUAUUCUCAAAUGCCACUACUGCUAGGUUGGUCCCCUCCCAACUUGCCCCUAUCCUUUUUUUAUUUUUAAGAAAAAAACUUUGUAAUGCUUGUGAUUCCAUCUGGGCAAAAGUCUGAAGAUCUGAAAUAACUUUAUAUCAAACCAUUGAUCAAUAAACAGCUACUAAUGAA